UUCAUCAAAAGUUUAUUGAGCAUCCAGUAUGUGCUAGGCACUCUGCUGGAUGCUAGUAAUACAAAGAUGAAGAUGAAAACAACACAAAAACAAACCCCACUUCCUUACUUACCCCUCCCCACCCCCAAUUUAAGGCAGAUUUGGCUUAAGCCUGGCAAGCUGGCCCCUCAGGGAUUCAGCACCAGGGUAUGGCAUGUUCUCAUCUCACCCUAACCUUCACCUGUGCAUCUCAAGGCUGACCAGCAGGUACUCCUUAUCCAAGUCCUGCUGCCUCUUCCACCUUCUUGAGAAACUUUUCCCCUACAUGCAUUAUCUCAUUAUGGAUGAGGCACCUGGGAAGUUUAGGGGAGCUGCGAAGGCACACCUGCUCAAAUGAGCCUGGGGAAGUGCCGAGGGACAGGGAGCUGAGACAGGCAUGCUGUGGGGUUCAGGGCAGAGGGGGCAAACUAGAAAUGUCAGUGCCUUUGGGGCUGAGACAAAACUUGACCUGGUGUGGAGGUGAUGGGUAACUGGGGCCUUGGAAUUGCUCCAUGGGUUGAUGGCGAAUCAGAGCUGGAGUUUAGGAGACUAGGGAUGCAAGGACCCUUGGAGGCAUUAAGGAGGAGGGAAUGGAAUACACAGAGGGCCUCCUUCUCUUUCAGCUUUUUAAUUGCCCUCUCUCCUCACACAGUAGAUUACUGCCACUCCUAUGAACUGUUCAAUAGGCGGUGGCAUGGGCAUGUCCUGGCUACACAGCGGCCCAGCCUCUUUAUUUUGAUGUUAGUGUGAUUAGGGAGUCUGCCCUUUUUCUGUGCCCUGGGACCUGAGCAUGUGGGAGCAGGGCAGAUGGGUGGCAGGAGGCCAGGGGUUGGAUCAUGUUCCCCCCAAAUGCUGGGAAGCAAUAAGCCUCCUCCUCCCCCCACCAUUUCUCUGGAGAUUAGGACUUAUUCUCACAGCUGGAGGAAGCUCAACAACUUUCCUGAGGACAAUGAUUGUUUGAAAGGCUUGUUUUGUAAGGAAGCCAGGAGGAAUAUAUGAGUUUGAUGAGCUAAAACAGUUCCUCAUUUGGUCUAGUUUUCGGGCCAGGGGAGUAAGUGAAAUUCACUUCUCUAUAAGAAUAAGCCCAUCCAUCUCUUUUAUUCAUGAACAGAGACAGAAAGAGUGCUUGGCAUGGCAUGCCUCCGAGGGAGGCUGUGGGAGGAGGCCAAGCUGGCAGGCUCGGGUUCUUUGCCCUUGCUAGCGCCCAGGUCAGAGGGAAAAGGAAUGUACUCGUACCCUUCCCUCACCACCUUGUAGGUCCCCAGGUACCAGGUGCCCAGGGAAGAAGGCCUUCACAAUGAUCCCCCCAGCUCAGAACAGCCCCUGCACACCCAGUAACCGGCAUCUGGCUUCUCCUUAGCUUAGUGCAGCUGUGGAUUCUGGGAAAGUGGCCUCUCUAAUCUGAACUUG